GGCAUUCUGGCGCGGAGCGGAGCGGCGGCGGGCGCAGCUAGCGGGUCGGCCGCGGAGCGGAGGUGCAGCUCGGCUUCCCCCGGCACCCCUCCCCCUCGGGCGCCAGCCCCACCCCUCCGCCGGCCGGGCCGACCCCGCCGUACUAUCCCCUGCGGCGCGAGCCCGGGGCGGCUCCAAGCGCCCCCCAGCAGACCCCCAUCAUGGGCAGCCAGAGCUCCAAGGCUCCCCGGGGCGACGUGACCGCCGAGGAGGCAGCAGGCGCUUCCCCCGCGAAGGCCAACGGCCAGGAGAAUGGCCACGUGAAAAGCAAUGGAGACUUAUCCCCCAAGGGUGAAGGGGAGUCGCCCCCUGUGAACGGAACAGAUGAGGCAGCCGGGGCCACUGGCGAUGCCAUCGAGCCAGCACCCCCUAGCCAGGGUGCUGAGGCCAAGGGGGAGGUCCCCCCCAAGGAGACCCCCAAGAAGAAGAAGAAAUUCUCUUUCAAGAAGCCUUUCAAAUUGAGCGGCCUGUCCUUCAAGAGAAAUCGGAAGGAGGGUGGGGGUGAUUCUUCUGCCUCCUCACCCACAGAGGAAGAGCAGGAGCAGGGGGAGAUCGGUGCCUGCAGCGACGAGGGCACUGCUCAGGAAGGGAAGGCCGCAGCCACCCCUGAGAGCCAGGAACCCCAGGCCAAGGGGGCAGAGGCUAGUGCAGCCUCAGAAGAAGAGGCAGGGCCCCAGGCUACAGAGCCAUCCACUCCCUCGGGGCCGGAGAGUGGCCCUACACCAGCCAGCGCUGAGCAGAAUGAGUAGCUAGGUAGGGGCAGGUGGGUGAUCUCUAAGCUGCAAAAACUGUGCUGUCCUUGUGAGGUCACUGCCUGGACCUGGUGCCCUGGCUGCCUUCCUGUGCCCAGAAAGGAAGGGGCUAUUGCCUCCUCCCAGCCACGUUCCCUUUCCUCCUCUCCCUCCUGUGGAUUCUCCCAUCAGCCAUCUGGUUCUCCUCUUAAGGCCAGUUGAAGAUGGUCCCUUACAGCUUCCCAAGUUAGGUUAGUGAUGUGAAAUGCUCCUGUCCCUGGCCCUACCUCCUUCCCUGUCCCCACCCCUGCAUAAGGCAGUUGUUGGUUUUCUUCCCCAAUUCUUUUCCAAGUAGGUUUUGUUUACCCUACUCCCCAAAUCCCUGAGCCAGAAGUGGGGUGCUUAUACUCCCAAACCUUGAGUGUCCAGCCUUCCCCUGUUGUUUUUAGUCUCUUGUGCUGUGCCUAGUGGCACCUGGGCUGGGGAGGACACUGCCCCGUCUAGGUUUUUAUAAAUGUCUUACUCAAGUUCAAACCUCCAGCCUGUGAAUCAACUGUGUCUCUUUUUUGACUUGGUAAGCAAGUAUUAGGCUUUGGGGUGGGGGGAGGUCUGUAAUGUGAAACAACUUCUUGUCUUUUUUUCUCCCACUGUUGUAAAUAACUUUUAAUGGCCAAACCCCAGAUUUGUACUUUUUUUUUUUUUCUAACUGCUAAAACCAUUCUCUUCCACCUGGUUUUACUGUAACAUUUGGAAAAGGAAUAAAUGUCGUCCCUUUA